ACUCACAGCAAAGCCUCAGACAAGAGAGGAACCUGGAGGGGAGGAGGUGGGAGGCCACCACUCAGCCGGCCUGGGGGCCAUGGGAGUCCAGCUGCCUGCCGUUAGUGGCCAGGAGCCCUCGUCCAUUGCGGCUCUUGAGAGCCCAAACUUGGCCACGGCAGGGCUCUUUCCCAUCAGGCCCUUUGAGCCCUGAUGGGAAACCCUUCCCCAGCCAGGGUGGGAUUUCUUGCUGCCGCCUGGAGCCGCCCUGGCCCUGUGGUUCUCAGGCCCUGGAGGAGUGAGGGGCUCCCCUGGUUACCCCAAGGGCACUCGUGGGGAUGAAGCCCGCGGGAUGCAGGAUUCCCACGAGACCUGUGCUGGCCACUGUGCGGGGUGGGGGGCUGCCAGGGAAGAGGUGCAGCCCCUGCCUGCCUCAGGGAUGCGAUCUGAGGGAAGAGGCAGCUGUGUCUGGGAGGCCGUUCGGUCGGAGGGGGAUAGGCACAGCCCCUGCCCUUGGGGAAGCGCCCAGCAGCAGCCUUCAGGGAAGGCAGUUUGGGGGUUUGCCGAGGGCCAGGAAGACCCUCUGCCGCAGUUAGUAUUCGAUGGAAUGGCUUGUGCAGAGGGAGCUGCAGAAGCUGCCAUUUCUCUGGGUUAGGGGCUCCCACAGCCUUUGGAUGCCGGGUCUCGGCCAUGAGCCCCCUCCGCCACCCCUCCCCCAGGUCACCUUGCUCAAUCCAGGAGGCCGGAUGAUCAGAGUGUGUUCUGCAAAGGAGCGUGAGAAUCACUGGGGAGAUUUCCUUUUUCUUUUUCUUUCUCUUUUUUUAAUGGUACAGCUUCCUGGGCCCACCCCUGAGAUUCUGCACUUGUUUGGGGAGUGGGUGUUGGCUUCAUGACAGGCACCCCUGGGUGCUUUGGACACAGGCAGUGAGCUCCCCCCACACUGUGUGAACCCCUGAGAAGGCUUCUCCUUUUGUCUAGGGUGCCUGGGAGUCUGCUCCAGCAGCAAACCGGGGAGGGGAGGGGUACUGGGACCGAGUGUGUGUGGCAGCACCGUGUCCAGGCAAACUGAGGCUCCAGACGGGGGUUACUUCUUCAGACCCUGUUAUGCAGCAUGGUUCCCACUGCCCGUGCCCAGAAUUCACCAUAGCUGAUGGGCCUGGGGUGGGCCUCCGGGGCAGGCCAGGGUGGAAAGUGCAUCUGUGUUUGAGCUUUGCGGCCCUGGCGCUGGAGUUAGAUCCCUACAGGAAAGGACAUUGUAACCCAGCCCGUGGUUGAGACUAGCAGCUGCUGAGCACCUACGCCCUGCUAGGCUGUGGGGCAACAGCAAAGGGUAACCCCCAGCCUGCAGCCUCAGGGGGGCUUCCCAUCUAGCGAGGGGCCCAGGGAGGCCAUGAGGAGAGCCAUGAGGGAGGAAGGUGGGGACUCUGGGCCUGAGUGACUCCUUCAGGGUGGGGUGCGGGCAGGGAGCCUUCAGGAGGGAGGGUACUGCCUGAGCAGGGCUCUUAAGGGACACGUGGAAUUUGUUACAGGAAGCACCAGGCCAUUCCAGGCAUAGAAAUCAGCUGGGGUGCAAAGGCCUGGGGGUCAGAAGAGUGGCAGAUUGCUCCAUGGCAGGAAGCCCCAGCUCCUCUGGGUCGUUCCCGCUGAGGGAUUCCAGCUGUUGGCACCGAGGGGUGCAGCCAGGGCAGGGUGGUGCUGCCUGCCAGGCUGAGGUGGGAGACAGCUGGGUUUCUAGCCCUGCUUGUCACUCGCUAUAGGUGCAGCCAAACGCUCAGCAGGCCCAAACUCUGGGCAGUCCUGACUCCCAGGCAGUGCUGUGAGGAAGGGGAGGAGGAGGCACACUGAACCCACCUGCUACGUUGGCUGGUGGAAAUUUGGCCAGGUCUGCACUGGCCCAGCGGUGCUGGGUGUCGUGACUGGUGUCUGCUCUGACUGGCUUGCUGACAGCUGAAGUCCAGGAUAGGUCCAUGGCCACGUUGUGCUGGUGGCAUUUACACCCUACGCCCCGGAGCCCGGGAGCACAUGCCGGCUCAGAGAAUACUAUGACCAGACAGCUCAGAUGUGCUGCAGCAAAUGCUCGCCGGGCCAACAUGCAAAAGUCUUCUGUACCAAGACCUCGGACACCGUGUGUGACUCCUGUGAGGACAGCACAUACACCCAGCUCUGGAACUGGGUUCCCGAGUGCUUGAGCUGUGGCUCCCGCUGUAGCUCUGACCAGGUGGAAACUCAAGCCUGCACUCGGGAACAGAACCGCAUCUGCACCUGCAGGCCCGGCUGGUACUGCGCGCUGAGCAAGCAGGAGGGGUGCCGGCUGUGCGCGCCGCUGCGCAAGUGCCGCCCGGGCUUCGGCGUGGCCAGACCAGGAACUGAAACAUCAGACGUGGUGUGCAAGCCCUGUGCCCCGGGGACGUUCUCCAACACGACUUCAUCCACGGAUAUUUGCAGGCCCCACCAGAUCUGUAACGUGGUGGCCAUCCCUGGGAAUGCAAGCAUGGAUGCAGUCUGCACGUCCACGUCCCCCACCCGGAGUAUGGCCCCAGGGGCAGUACACUUACCCCAGCCAGUGUCCACACGAUCCCAACACACGCAGCCAACUCCAGAACCCAGCACUGCUCCAAGCACCUCCUUCCUGCUCCCAAUGGGCCCCAGCCCCCCAGCUGAAGGGAGCACUGGCGACUUCGCUCUUCCAGUUGGACUGAUUGUGGGUGUGACAGCCUUGGGUCUACUAAUAAUAGGAGUGGUGAACUGUGUCAUCAUGACCCAGGUGAAAAAGAAGCCCUUGUGCCUGCAGAGAGAAGCCAAGGUGCCUCACUUGCCUGCCGAUAAGGCCCGGGGUACACAGGGCCCCGAGCAGCAGCACCUGCUGAUCACAGCGCCGAGCUCCAGCAGCAGCUCCCUGGAGAGCUCGGCCAGUGCGUUGGACAGAAGGGCGCCCACUCGGAACCAGCCACAGGCACCAGGCGUGGAGGCCAGUGGGGCCGGGGAGGCCCGGGCCAGCACCGGGAGCUCAGGACUGUCAGACUGCAUGUACAGACAUUGUCUUCUCCUGUCUCCCACGCCAGGCUGUGGGACACCUGCAGAUUCUUCCCCUGGUGGCCAUGGGACCCAGGUCAAUGUCACCUGCAUCGUGAACGUCUGUAGCAGCUCUGACCACAGCUCACAGUGCUCCUCCCAAGCCAGCUCCACAAUGGGAGACACAGAUUCCAGCCCCUCGGAGUCCCCGAAGGACGAGCAGGUCCCCUUCUCCAAGGAGGAAUGUGCCUUUCGGUCACAGCUGGAGACGCCAGAGACCCUGCUGGGGAGCACCGAAGAGAAGCCCCUGCCCCUUGGAGUGCCUGAUGCUGGGAUGAAGCCCAGUUAACCAGGCCGGUGUGGGCUGUGUCGUAGCCAAGGUGGGCUGAGCCCUGGCAGGAUGACCCUGCGAAGGGGCCCUGGUCCUUCCAGGCCCCCACCACUAGGACUCUGAGGCUCUUUCUGGGCCAAGUUCCUCUAGUGCCCUCCACAGCCGCAGCCUCCCUCUGACCUGCAGGCCAAGAGCAGAGGCAGCGAGUUGUGGAAAGCCUCUGCUGCCAUGGCGUGUCCCUCUCGGAAGGCUGGCUGGGCAUGGACGUUCGGGGCAUGCUGGGGCAAGUCCCUGACUCUCUGUGACCUGCCCCGCCCAGCUGCACCUGCCAGCCUGGCUUCUGGAGCCCUUGGGUUUUUUGUUUGUUUGUUUGUUUGUUUGUUUGUUUCUCCCCCUGGGCUCUGCCCCAGCUCUGGCUUCCAGAAAACCCCAGCAUCCUUUUCUGCAGAGGGGCUUUCUGGAGAGGAGGGAUGCUGCCUGAGUCACCCAUGAAGACAGGACAGUGCUUCAGCCUGAGGCUGAGACUGCGGGAUGGUCCUGGGGCUCUGUGCAGGGAGGAGGUGGCAGCCCUGUAGGGAACGGGGUCCUUCAAGUUAGCUCAGGAGGCUUGGAAAGCAUCACCUCAGGCCAGGUGCAGUGGCUCACGCCUAUGAUCCCAGCACUUUGGGAGGCUGAGGCGGGUGGAUCACCUGAGGUUAGGAGUUCGAGACCAGCCUGGCCAACAUGGUAAAACCCCAUCUCUACUAAAAAUACAGAAAUUAGCCGGGCGUGGUGGCGGGCACCUAUAGUCCCAGCUACUCAGAAGCCUGAGGCUGGGAAAUCGUUUGAACCCGGGAAGCGGAGGUUGCAGGGAGCCGAGAUCACGCCACUGCACUCCAGCCUGGGCGACAGAGCGAGAGUCUGUCUCAAAAGAAAAAAAAAAGCACCGCCUCCAAAUGCCAACUUGUCCUUUUGUACCAUGGUGUGAAAGUCAGAUGCCCAGAGGGCCCAGGCAGGCCACCAUAUUCAGUGCUGUGGCCUGGGCAAGAUAACGCACUUCUAACUAGAAAUCUGCCAAUUUUUUAAAAAAGUAAGUACCACUCAGGCCAACAAGCCAACGACAAAGCCAAACUCUGCCAGCCACAUCCAACCCCCCACCUGCCAUUUGCACCCUCCGCCUUCACUCCGGUGUGCCUGCAGCCCCGCGCCUCCUUCCUUGCUGUCCUAGGCCACACCAUCUCCUUUCAGGGAAUUUCAGGAACUAGAGAUGACUGAGUCCUCGUAGCCAUCUCUCUACUCCUACCUCAGCCUAGACCCUCCUCCUCCCCCAGAGGGGUGGGUUCCUCUUCCCCACUCCCCACCUUCAAUUCCUGGGCCCCAAACGGGCUGCCCUGCCACUUUGGUACAUGGCCAGUGUGAUCCCAAGUGCCAGUCUUGUGUCUGCGUCUGUGUUGCGUGUCGUGGGUGUGUGUAGCCAAGGUCGGUAAGUUGAAUGGCCUGCCUUGAAGCCACUGAAGCUGGGAUUCCUCCCCAUUAGAGUCAGCCUUCCCCCUCCCAGGGCCAGGGCCCUGCAGAGGGGAAACCAGUGUAGCCUUGCCCGGAUUCUGGGAGGAAGCAGGUUGAGGGGCUCCUGGAAAGGCUCAGUCUCAGGAGCAUGGGGAUAAAGGAGAAGGCAUGAAAUUGUCUAGCAGAGCAGGGGCAGGGUGAUAAAUUGUUGAUAAAUUCCACUGGACUUGAGCUUGGCAGCUGAACUAUUGGAGGGUGGGAGAGCCCAGCCAUUACCAUGGAGACAAGAAGGGUUUUCCACCCUGGAAUCAAGAUGUCAGACUGGCUGGCUGCAGUGACGUGCACCUGUACUCAGGAGGCUGAGGGGAGGAUCACUGGAGCCCAGGAGUUUGAGGCUGCAGCGAGCUAUGAUCGCGCCACUACACUCCAGCCUGAGCAACAGAGUGAGACCCUGUCUCUUAAAGAAAAAAAAAGUCAGACUGCUGGGACUGGCCAGGUUUCUGCCCACAUUGGACCCACAUGAGGACAUGAUGGAGCGCACCUGCCCCCUGGUGGACAGUCCUGGGAGAACCUCAGGCUUCCUUGGCAUCACAGGGCAGAGCCGGGAAGCGAUGAAUUUGGAGACUCUGUGGGGCCUUGGUUCCCUUGUGUGUGUGUGUUGAUCCCAAGACAAUGAAAGUUUGCACUGUAUGCUGGACGGCAUUCCUGCUUAUCAAUAAACCUGUUUGUUUUA